ACUCGGCCUUCUGGGCGCGCGCGACGUCAGUUUGAGUUCUGUGUUCUCCCCGCCCGUGUCCCGCCCGACCCGCGCCCGCGAUGCUGGCGCUGCGCUGCGGCUCCCGCUGGCUCGGCCUGCUCUCCGUCCCGCGCUCCGUGCCGCUGCGCCUCCCCGCGGCCCGCGCCUGCAGCAAGGGCUCCGGCGACCCGUCCUCUUCCUCCUCCUCCGGGAACCCGCUCGUGUACCUGGACGUGGACGCCAACGGGAAGCCGCUCGGCCGCGUGGUGCUGGAGCUGAAGGCAGAUGUCGUCCCAAAGACAGCUGAGAACUUCAGAGCCCUGUGCACUGGUGAGAAGGGCUUCGGCUACAAAGGCUCCACCUUCCACAGGGUGAUCCCUUCCUUCAUGUGCCAGGCGGGCGACUUCACCAACCACAAUGGCACAGGCGGGAAGUCCAUCUACGGAAGCCGCUUUCCUGACGAGAACUUUACACUGAAGCACGUGGGGCCAGGUGUCCUGUCCAUGGCUAAUGCUGGUCCUAACACCAACGGCUCCCAGUUCUUCAUCUGCACCAUAAAGACAGACUGGUCCAUGGCAUUGGAUGACAUUGCGCUACACUGUUGCUCACCCGGGUCACCCGUCCUCACAGGUUGGAUGGCAAGCAUGUUGUGUUCGGUCACGUCAAAGAGGGCAUGGACGUCGUGAAGAAAAUAGAAUCUUUCGGCUCUAAGAGUGGGAGGACAUCCAAGAAGAUUGUCAUCACAGACUGUGGCCAGUUGAGCUAAUCUGUGGCCAGGGUGCUGGCAUGGUGGCAGCUGCAAAUGUCCAUGCACCCAGGUGGCCGCGUUGGGCUGUCAGCCAAGGUGCCUGAAACGAUACGUGUGCCCACUCCACUGUCACAGUGUGCCUGAGGAAGGCUGCUAGGGAUGUUAGACCUCGGCCAGGACCCACCACAUUGCUUCCUAAUACCCACCCUUCCUCACGACCUCAUUUCUGGGCAUCUUUGUGGACAUGAUGUCACCCACCCCUUGUCAAGCAUUGCCUGUGAUUGCCCAGCCCAGAUUCAUCUGUGCCUUGGACAUGGUGAUGGUGAUGGGUUGCCAUCCAAGUGAAAGUCUUUUCCUUGACCAAGGGGGACAGUCAGUUUUGCAAAAGGACUCUAAUACCUGUUUAAUAUUGUCUUCCUAAUUGGGAUAAUUUAAUUAACAAGAUUGACUAGAAGUGAAACUGCAACACUAACUUCCCCGUGCUGUGGUGUGACCUGAGUUGGUGACACAGGCCACAGACCCCAGAGCUUGGCUUUUGAAACACAACUCAGGGCUUUUGUGAAGGUUCCCCCGCUGAGAUCUUUCCUCCUGGUUACUGUGAAGCCUGUUGGUUUGCUGCUGUCGUUUUUGAGGAGGGCCCAUGGGGGUAGGAGCAGUUGAACCUGGGAACAAACCUCACUUGAGCUGUGCCUAGACAAUGUGAAUUCCUGUGUUGCUAACAGAAGUGGCCUGUAAGCUCCUGUGCUCCGGAGGGAAGCAUUUCCUGGUAGGCUUUGAUUUUUCUGUGUGUUAAAGAAAUUCAAUCUACUCAUGAUGUGUUAUGCAUAAAACAUUUCUGGAACAUGGAUUUGUGUUCACCUUAAAUGUGAAAAUAAAUCCUAUUUUCUAUGGAAGACUGGUACCUGGUUUCUGGAAGAGGGGUCUGUGACUUGGAGCUGAUCUUUACUGAGCUCGCCGUGGCAGAUGCCAUGCUCAGGACGUUCAUGUGGAUGGUUUCAUGUCAUCGUGCUGGCAACUUGUCCUCCCUGCCUUAGAGAUGAGGCUCAGACAAACGACCUUAGCACCCAUAGCCUAUGCCAUGAGCACUGGCUCCACCCUGAAUCCCAGCUCCUCCCCUUAGUGACCCCAAGUCUGUUUCCCUCAGCUGCAUAAGGAGGCGAUAUAGUUUGAAUAUUUGUCCCCAGCCAAAUCUCAUGUUGAACUGUAAUCCCCAGUGCUGGAGGUGGGGCCUGCUACGAGGUGUUUGGAUCAUGGGGACGGGUAUUUCAUGGCUUGGUGCUGUUUUCUUGAUGGUGAAUUAUUGCAAGAUACGGUCAUUUAAAAUUGUGUGGCACCUCCCCCUGCCCCCUUCUUGCUCCUGCUUUCACCAUGUGACAUGCCUGAUCCCCCUUCACCUUUUGCCAUGGUCAUAAGCUUCCUGAGGCCUCCCUGGAAGCUGAGCAGAUGCCAGCACCAUGCUUCCUGUACAUCCUGCAGAACCAUAAGCCAAUUAAACCUUUUUAAUAAUAAA